CGGCGGGUGGGGAGCGGCAGGCGGGCAGGGUCCCCGGAGGCCCCCGGGCUCUGCCCCUCCAGCUAGAGAGGCAGCCGAACCCUAGCGGCCUGGAAGGGGCCGGGAAACCGCGGCCAGCUGGCAAGGAGUGGCCCCCGGGGGCGGGGCGCCGGCGGGUGUGUGAGUAGCCCGCCCGGCCCGGGUCCGAGUUCCAGCCCCGCGAUGGCCUCCGCGGGCAGCACCGCUCGGCGGGCGGGCUCCGGAAGCUGGCACUCAGAAAGGGGAGAAGGGAGAGGUGCUCGGCCGCAGCCAACUCCAAGUGGCUCCAUGCAGCAGGCGAACAAAGUCUCCUUGAAGGCCACCUGGACUGACGCGGAGUCCAAGCAGCCCAGCCCCAGCAAGGAGUCCGACCAGACGGCAAUCGACCAGACGGCGAUCGGGAGCUACUACCAGCUGUUCGCAGCGGCUGUGGGCAACGUGGAAUGGCUGCGAUUCUGUCUGAACCAGAGCCUCAGGGAAAUCCCCACCGACGACAAGGGCUUCACUGCCAUCCACUUCGCCGCCCAAUGGGGCAAGCUUGCAUGCCUGCAGGUCCUGGUAGAGGAGUACAAGUUUCCCGUGGACCUGCUGACCAACAAUAGCCAGACACCCCUGCACCUCGUCAUCCACAGGGACAACACCACCGUGGCCCUCCCCUGCAUCUACUACCUGCUGGAGAAAGGCGCAGACCUCAAUGCUCAGACAUGCAACGGCUCCACGCCCCUGCACCUGGCAGCCCGUGACGGCUUGCUGGACUGUGUGAAGGUCCUGGUGCAGAGUGGCGCCAACGUCCAUGCCCAAGAUGCCAUGGGCUACAAACCCAUUGACUUCUGCAAAAUAUGGAACCACCGUGCCUGUGCCCGGUUCUUGAAGGAUGCCAUGUGGAAAAAGGACAAGAAGGACUUUGCCCGUGAGAUGACGAAAAUGAAGAUGUUCAAGAGCCAGCUGACCCUCAUGGAGCACAACUACCUGAUUGAGUAUCAAGGUCAAGGAUGCAGUGUGCACUUCCCAUUUGCCUUUUCCCCCAUCACACCAGAGACUCUCCUAUGGCAGGACAUUUCUCUACUAUCAGACUGUGGAUUCCUUUGGAGAAGAAGGGAAUUGUCUUUCUAAAGAGCACAAAAUUCUCAGAGAAGCUGCUAUCAGAAAGUGGCUCCACGGCAAGCUGCACCCAGGCCACUCUCUGGUCUCCAAUACCAAGCAAGCCCGGGCCACCGCCCUCUCCAAGACCCCAGAGCAACGGGAAUCGCAGCGUUCCAGGAGCUUCCACCCCUCUGUGGAUGCACGCCUGCAAUGCAUUCCACAGCCCACGGAGAUGCCCAAGCCCAUCUACAGGAAGCCCACGGUCAAGCGGCCCACAAUGUGGAAUGUUAGCAACAACCCCGCCAGACCCCCCACCACCCAGAUCAGCCACUCGCAGGGCAUCCGCCUGGGCGUGCAUCCAGACCCCACUCCGGAGCACGACUUCAGCAGCUUCCUGGAGGUGAGGCCUGAUGGGCACGGCGGUGCGCGGCUGCACACAGUGGACGGCCACUGGGUGGCGCCCGUGCCGCGGCUGCCUUUUGAGGUGCUGCUGCGCAUGCUGUACCCACGUGUAUGGCCAUACAGAAUGAAGGUGCCCCAGGGCUUUUACCCCAUCAGCAUGAGGGAAGUGCCCAGGAAGCGGCACCUGGGUGACAACACCUUCUGGACCGACACUCUGGCCAUGAACCUGCGUGACACAUUCGAUGAAGCCUUCCUGGCAGCUGUGCGAUCUCAUCAAGGACUCCCCACCCUGCCCUCCCCACAAACCAACCCAUAAAGUUAUUAUGGCUACCUCUCCCCCUGAGGCAGCCCAGUGAAGGCUGAAGUGUGGCAAUUCACGUUGUGGGUGGCGAGGAAAGGGGGAGGGGUGCCUAUGGGCUUCCCACUCCCAAGCUCGAGGAGUCACCCUUCCCAAUCAAAAGCCCAGACCCCAGGCCUCCCUUUUCUCUGCAAAUAAAUCUCUUGGCACCCCCCCA